GACUCGGCUAAUGGCGUCGGCGAGUCUUAGGGGCCUGGGGAGCUGGCGCUGAAGCUUCUUGCCAGGUUGGCUGGUGACACCCGGUGUGGCUGGGCCCCGCGGCAGCGGAGGGACCUGCCCGCCUUGUGGGUUUCUCGGCCAGAGUCGGCGGAGCCUAGCGGGACGGUGCGACUGCGGGGGGCGCCUCCGAGAAAAGCCAGAGGUGUUGCGGGGAAGCUGCUGGGGGACGCUCGAGCAGGCUCCGGGUUCGCAGCCCAGGGCCCAAGAAGCGGGCUGCUGAAGGACCAGAGACACCGGGAGGGAGCUGCCUGUGGCCCUAAGGAGCUGACCGUGCCAGAGCUUGUUUGUACCUCUCGGAAAUUGGCUGGGACCUUGGAGGAUCAUGUCCGGCACCAGCAGCCCCGAGGCGGUGAAGAAGCUGCUGGAGAAUAUGCAGAGCGACUUGCGCGCCUUGUCACUGGAGUGCAAGAAGAAAUUCCCACCUGUCAAAGAGGUACAGAUGAGGGGUAUCUAACUGAGCCUGGAAGUUGGAGGAGGGGAGUCAUUCCUAGCAGAGGAAAUAGCACACGUUGCUGCUGAAUCAGGAAUAAUAAAAGUUAAAACAAUUGCUGCACGAAACACUGAAAUUUUGGCAGGAUAAAAACUGCAAUUAUGCAGUGAAACUGCUCAGAGCAAGGAAACCCCUAGGAUAUGGGGACCUGGUGGACCUUUUUCAGCACUGAAAGAGAACAGCUCAGAGGUUGUACAGCCUUUUUUAAUGGGUUGUGGAACCAAGGAACCGAAGAUCACUCAGCUAUGUUUGGCUGCUAUUCAGAGACUCAUGUCACAUGAAGUCGUGUCUGAGACUGCAGCUGGAAAUAUAAUUAACAUGCUUUGGCAGCUAAUGGAGAAUAGUCUUGAAGAACUUAAGCUACUUCAAACAGUUCUUGUUCUUUUAACAACCAAUACAGUAGUUCAUGAUGAGGCACUUUCUAAGGCAAUCGUUCUUUGUUUUCGACUACACUUCACAAAAGAUAAUAUUACAAAUAAUACAGCUGCUGCUACAGUGCGACAAGUUGUUACUGUUGUUUUUGAGAGGAUGGUUGCUGAAGAUGAACGACACAGAGAUAUUAUAGAACAACCAGUACUGGUACAAGGAAAUAGUAACAGAAGAUCUGUCAGUACCCUCAAACCUUGUGCUAAAGAUGCAUAUAUGCUUUUCCAGGAUCUUUGUCAGUUGGUUAAUGCUGAUGCUCCUUAUUGGCUAGUGGGCAUGACAGAAAUGACUCGGACGUUUGGCCUCGAAUUACUUGAGUCAGUCCUCAAUGAUUUUCCGCAGGUCUUUUUACAACACCAAGAAUUUAGUUUCCUCCUCAAAGAAAGGGUAUGUCCUCUUGUGAUAAAGCUCUUUUCUCCAAAUAUAAAGUUCAGACAAGGUUCCAGCACCUCAUCUUCUCCAGCACCAGUUGAAAAACCAUAUUUUCCUAUCUGCAUGCGUUUGCUGAGAGUAGUAUCUGUUCUGAUUAAGCAGUUUUACAGUCUUUUGGUAACUGAAUGUGAGAUAUUUCUGUCACUUCUGGUGAAAUUUCUGGAUGCAGAUAAACCACAGUGGCUACGAGCUGUUGCGGUGGAAUCAAUACACAGAUUCUGUGUGCAGCCUCAACUAUUAAGGUCAUUUUGUCAGUCCUAUGAUAUGAAACAGCAUUCUACCAAGGUUUUUCGUGAUAUUGUAAAUGCACUGGGAUCUUUUAUACAGUCCUUGUUUCUUGUCCCCCCUACUGGAAAUCCUGCAACAAGCAACCAAGCUGGAAACAAUAAUUUAGGUGGCUCAGUCUCAGCACCAGCUAACUCAGGAAUGGUGGGGAUUGGUGGAGGUGUUACUUUGCUACCAGCAUUUGAAUAUAGGGGAACCUGGAUACCUAUUCUGACAAUCACAGUUCAAGGCAGUGCUAAAGCCACCUACUUAGAAAUGUUGGACAAAGUUGAGCCUCCAACUAUACCUGAAGGUUACGCCAUGUCUGUGGCAUUCCAUUGUUUGCUAGACCUUGUUCGUGGAAUCACAAGUAUGAUUGAAGGAGAGCUAGGAGAGCUUGAAACAGAAUGUCAAACCACCACUGAAGAAGGUUCUUCACCAACACAGUCGACAGAACAGCAGGAUUUACAGUCAACAUCAGACCAAAUGGAUAAGGAAAUUGUUAGUAGGGCUGUUUGGGAAGAAAUGGUGAAUGCCUGCUGGUGUGGUCUUCUUGCUGCACUCUCACUCCUUCUUGAUGCCAGCACAGAUGAAGCUGCCACUGAGAAUAUUUUAAAAGCUGAACUGACUAUGGCUGCUCUUUGUGGAAGACUGGGCCUUGUAACUUCAAGAGAUGCCUUUAUAACUGCAAUAUGCAAAGGUUCCCUGCCUCCCCAUUAUGCUCUUACUGUAUUGAAUACCACCACUGCAGCUACACUUUCCAACAAAUCAUAUUCCGUUCAGGGCCAAAGUGUUAUGAUGAUAAGUCCAUCAAGUGAAUCUCACCAACAAGUUGUGGCAGUGGGUCAACCUUUAGCAGUCCAGCCUCAAGGGACAGUAAUGCUGACUUCCAAAAAUAUCCAGUGUAUGAGGACUUUACUUAACUUGGCGCAUUGCCAUGGGGCUGUUCUUGGAACAUCAUGGCAACUUGUCUUGGCAACUCUUCAGCAUCUUGUGUGGAUUCUGGGAUUAAAGCCUAGUAGUGGCGGUGCCUUGAAACCUGGGAGAGCUGUAGAAGGACCCAGUACAGUUCUAACAACAGCAGUGAUGACAGAUUUACCAGUGAUUUCCAAUAUACUUUCAAGAUUGUUUGAAAGCUCACAGUAUCUUGAUGAUGUAUCACUGCAUCAUUUAAUAAAUGCACUUUGCUCCUUGUCUCUAGAAGCAAUGGAUAUGGCCUAUGGAAAUAAUAAGGAACCAUCUCUUUUUGCUGUUGCCAAAUUGUUAGAAACUGGUUUAGUUAAUAUGCACCGAAUAGAAAUUCUGUGGAGACCUCUGACUGGCCAUCUACUUGAGAAGGUCUGCCAGCAUCCAAACUCUCGAAUGAGAGAAUGGGGAGCAGAAGCUUUAACUUCUCUUAUUAAAGCAGGAUUAACAUUUAACCAUGAUCCUCCACUCUCACAAAACCAGAGGCUGCAGUUGCUUUUAUUGAACCCGUUAAAGGAGAUGUCCAAUAUUAAUCAUCCAGAUAUUCGACUCAAGCAGUUAGAAUGCGUGUUGCAGAUUCUGCAGAGUCAGGGAGACAGUCUUGGGCCUGGAUGGCCAUUAGUGCUUGGAGUCAUGGGAGCAAUCAGAAAUGAUCAAGGAGAAUCCUUGAUACGAACUGCAUUCCAGUGUCUUCAGUUGGUUGUGACAGAUUUUCUACCAACAAUGCCUUGUACUUGCCUGCAAAUAGUUGUAGAUGUUGCAGGUAGCUUUGGCCUCCAUAACCAAGAACUCAAUAUUAGUUUAACUUCAAUAGGUUUAUUGUGGAAUAUUUCAGAUUAUUUUUUCCAAAGAGGGGAAACUAUUGAAAAAGAACUAAAUAAGGAAGAGGCAGCACAGCAAAAGCAGGCAGAAGAGAAAGGAGUUGUUUUAAAUCGGCCAUUCCACCCUGCACCGCCAUUUGAUUGCUUGUGGUUAUGUCUUUAUGCAAAAUUGGGUGAACUAUGUGUGGAUCCCCGUCCUGCUGUCAGGAAGAGUGCAGGGCAAACUCUGUUUUCUACAAUUGGUGCGCAUGGAACUUUAUUACAGCAUUCAACCUGGCACACUGUUAUCUGGAAGGUACUCUUUCAUCUACUGGACAGAGUUCGAGAGUCCUCUACCACUGCAGACAAAGAAAAGAUUGAGUCUGGAGGUGGCAAUAUUCUCAUUCAUCAUUCAAGGGACACCGCCGAGAAGCAAUGGGCUGAGACGUGGGUAUUAACAUUGGCUGGAGUAGCAAGGAUCUUCAACACUAGAAGAUAUUUGCUGCAGCCUUUAGGAGAUUUUUCAAGAGCUUGGGAUGUUCUUCUUGACCAUAUACAGUCAGCAGCACUCAGCAAAAACAAUGAAGUAUCUCUGGCUGCUCUGAAAAGCUUCCAGGAAAUUUUACAGAUUGUGUCCCCUGUCAGAGACUCAGAUAAGCCUGAGACACCACCUGUAGUUAAUGUACCUGUGCCUGUUCUUAUAGGGCCCAUAUCAGGCAUGAGCAGGCCAUUUGUAAGAACAGAUUCCAUUGGAGAAAAACUAGGAAGAUAUAGUAGCUCUGAGCCACCCAUUGUUACUGAUGAGCUUGAAGAUUUGAAUCUAUGGUGGGCUGCGUGGAAUACCUGGUAUAGAAUUGGAUCUGAAAGUACUAAGCCUCCUAUUACUUUUGAUAAACUAACUUUUAUUCCUAGCCAGCCUUUUCUUACAGCUUUAAUUCAGAUAUUUCCAGCUCUCUACCAACACAUAAAAACUGGUUUCAAUAUGGAUGACUUGCAAAAGUUGGGAGUCAUAUUGCACAGUGCUAUUUCAGUCCCAAUAAGUUCAGAUGCAUCCCCUUUUAUUCUUCCAUCUUAUACCGAAGCAGUUUUGACAAGUUUACAGGAAGCUGUACUUACAGCUUUAGAUGUUCUCCAAAAGGCCAUUUGUGUAGGACCAGAAAACAUGCAGAUAAUGUAUCCAGCUAUAUUUGACCAGUUGUUGGCAUUUGUAGAAUUUUCCUGUAAACCUCCACAGUAUGGACAGCUGGAAACAAAGCACAUUGCAAAUGCAAAAUAUAAUCAGAUCCAACUAUUUGCACCGGCGGAAUGGGUAGCCUUGAAUUAUGUGCCGUUUGCUGAAAGGUCUUUAGAAGUAGUUGUGGAUUUAUACCAAAAAACAGCGUGUCACAAAGCAGUGGUGAAUGAGAAAGUGCUCCAGAAUAUUAUUAAGACUCUUAGGGUUCCUCUCAGUUUGAAGUAUUCCUGCCCUUCUGAAAGCACAUGGAAACUAGCAGUAUCCUCUCUCCUCAGAGUUCUUUCUAUUGGGCUACCUGUUGCCCGGCAGCAUGCUUCUUCUGGAAAAUUUGACAGUAUGUGGCCAGAACUAGCCAAUACUUUUGAAGAUUUUCUCUUUACUAAAAGCAUACCUCCAGAUAAUCUCUCUAUUCAAGAGUUUCAAAGAAAUGAAAAUAUUGAUGUCGAGGUAGUUCAACUUAUCAGCAAUGAGAUACUACCUUAUGCCAAUUUUAUUCCUAAGGAAUUUGUUGGUCAAAUAAUGACAAUGCUUAACAAGGGCUCAAUACAUUCUCAGUCAUCUUCAUUUACAGAAGCAGAGAUUGAUAUUCGUUUGAGAGAGGAAUUUUCUAAAAUGUGUUUUGAAACAUUACUCCAGUUUUCCUUCAGUAAUAAAGUCACAACACCUCAAGAAGGCUACAUCUCACGAAUGGCACUCUCAGUGCUUUUAAAGAGGUCCCAAGAUGUACUACAUCGCUAUAUAGAGGAUGAAAGAUUAAGUGGUAAAUGCCCUCUUCCAAGGCAACAAGUAACAGAAAUUAUAUUUGUUUUAAAAGCAGUCAGUACUCUUAUUGAUUCACUUAAGAAAACUCAGCCUGAGAAUGUUGAUGGAAAUACCUGGGCACAAGUAAUUGCCUUAUACCCAACUUUAGUAGAAUGCAUCACCUGUUCUUCUUCAGAAGUCUGUUCUGCACUUAAAGAGGCACUAGUUCCUUUUAAGGAUUUCAUGCAGCCACCAGCAUCCAGAGUUCAAAAUGGAGAAUCUUGACCGGCUACAAUAUAUUUGAAAGCAGGAAGAUAGUCUAAAAAAUGUUUGCUCCUAAUUGAGUCUUCUGUGAGAAGGACAUUUCUUACUGCAGAUAAUUCUUGGCAGCUGUUGUUGGCCUCCUUUAAAUUCUACUUACCUGAGUUCAGUAAUUCAUAUUACAGGCUUGCACAUCAACAAAGGCUCCUGAAUGAACAGCAGUGUAAGGCUUUAAUAAAUUAAACUGAUGGGAGGGAUAAUUAACACUACAGUAUACAUGCUACCAUAUCUCCAGUUGGUGAUUUAAAGUGAGCUUAUGUACAGUUUGUGGUGUAUGUGUUAAUGAUGUACUUUUUAAAAAGAAAGAAGAGAUAUUUCAAUUCAGUCAGAUUUAUUAGUCUGGUGUUUUUGCACCCUUUUUCAAGUACAAAAUCGUACUAGAAUUUUAUGCAAGAUGGUACUGUAACAUUCCAUAUUAUCUAUAACCAGCCUUUGUUAACAAAGGGAACUGAUAUACUUGUGUGUAUAAUAAAUGGUACAGUUCUGUAUAAAAUAGUGCAUUUAUUUAAAUUUUAAAAGUAUUGAUAAUGUUAAAUGCUUAAAGCUCUAUUUAUUAUUAAUACAAAAUUGUUUGCUUACAUUUUUACUUAUAAUUUGCCUUCAUAUGUGGCGGAUAAGCUCACCAUAUGAUCAUGCAGUUAGCUUCAUGCUUAUUUUAAAUGUAUUAUUAGUGACCAUUAAACAUCUGACCAGUAAGGUCAUGUGAACACAGCAGCAAAUAGUUUAUGAUUUGCUGAUUUUGGAGCUUUGAAAUAUAGGUUCUUAAUACAUUGAUACAUAUUGUAGCACUAUGACUUCAUCAUACCUCAUUUCUUUAAACAGCUCUCCAAGCUUUCACUGAAGUCUGUCUGUUUUUUAUAUUGGCUGUCUGGAUUUUAAAGACUUUUCAUAUUUUAUAUUUCUACUGAUUUUGUUUCCCCUAACAACAUUUGUCACUGUCUUUGAAUUAUGACCCAGGCAAGAUGAUUUCAGAUUUUCUAAAAUCUUGCCUGUGAGGUUUUGUUCAUAUCAGUGCUUCAUUUUGUAAUGUCUUCUCAAGAAAAAUACCUAUGUUAACUCACAAGUAUAAAAUAUGUGUGUAUUAUAAAACAAUGAAAAGUGUAUUUUUGGAGAUAGUCAAGCAUUUAGAAGUGCAGUGAACUUGCUGUCACGGAGUAAAAUGCUAAUUAUGUUUCACUUUCCUAGCCUAGUGAAAAAGAAAAGUGCUCUUGAGUACAAUACCUUAAUUAUUUCUUAAAAUACUGACUUUGACCUAGCUCACUGUAUUUUUUAUUUAAUGGAUUAUGGAUUACAGUAUUUUUCUUCUGAGUUAAAUUUUCAUAAUUUAUGUGAAGACACAAAGAUGUUUAAAACAAUGAUUAUUCAUAAGAAAUCAUGAUGGUCUCAGUAUUAUUUUAGUGUAUUGGAAGGUCUUUGAUCUUAAUAGAAUUUAUAAAUUUCAGCUUCUCCAGAAUAAUCAUAAAACUGCAAAAAGAUAUUAUAAUUGAGUCAUGAUUGAGAUACAGUUUUGAGGCUAUUAUAAUUGUAUAAUUAUUUAAUUUGCAUUAUCUGUAAAAUGUAGUAAGGUCUUUGAGGGGAUAUUUUUUAUUUACAUGAAUUACUGAAUUUCUAUUUUAUUAUUUCACCUAAAAUUAAGGUAAAAUAUGGCAUUUCAUAAGUUCUGCUUUCAGCAUUUUCCUUAAAGUUGUAAAAAAUCAAGCUAUGUACUUAUUUUCUAUAUUUGGGUGUGUUAAAUUGAGGAUUAGAAAAAUCCACAUAAUCACUGAUAAAGCAUUGAAACAGAAUAACCCAAGGGUAGUGUACCGAUUCAGUAACAUGUUAAAAAUAUUGCUAUGCAUUUAUUCAAAGGAAAAUGGUCUGUUCUUGAGAAAUAAAAGAUCAGUUGCAAUUAGGAUAAUUAAAUAGUUAAAUAUGAGUCAAGUGUAUGCAAUAUACAUUUAUAUGAACCAAAGCUUGCUUUAUCAGGACCAUGCCCUACAGUUCAAAACAUAAACAUAGUGAAUGUGUUAAUAUCAUAUAAUAAGGUAAUAAAUGCCAGUCUUAGUGUGAAGCAAGUGGGUGGCCCCCUUGGUAGUAUAAUUGGACAGGAUUUUCCUCCAGAAUAUUUCCUGUCACCCUCCAAGAGUCACUACAGUAAUUGAUUGCUGGCAUGGAACACAUUGCCCUUGUCUUGUUAGUAUGAAUUGGGUUCUCCAGUGACUAGAAGAACUGGGGUGUGUGAAAGUAUUCGAUGCCAGGAGAUUCAAAAAGGAAGCUCUCAAAGAUAAGAUCAUUUUAUGGCACAAUUGAGUCUAUAACCAGCCCUUUAAGCAGUAGUAAAAAUGUCCUUUGUCAUACUUACUAGAAAUACUAUGAGUUUUUUUUUUUUUUUUCAUUUGAGACGGAGUCUCGCUCUGUCACCCAGGCUGGAAUGCAGUGGCACGAUCUUGGCUCACUGCAACCUCUGCUUCCCGGGUUCAAGCAGUUUCCUGCUUCAGACUUCCAAGUAGCUGGGAUUACAGACAUGCCACCAUGCCAGGCUAAUUUUUUUAAUAUUUUUAGUAGAGAUGGGGUUUCACCAUUUUGGCCAUUCUAGUCUUGAACUCCUGACCUCAGGUGAUCUGCCCGCCUUGGCCUCCCAAAGUGCUGACAUUACAGGCCUGAGCCACUGCGCCCAGCCAAUACCAUGAGUUUUAAGCCUCACAUCGUCACUUGCUGUCACUGCCAGUGCCUGUUUUAUUCAUAUUGCUGGACAACAGACAUAUGCCACCAAUUGUAUGAUUAAUAAAGUCUUUUUCUGGCCAUUUUGUCCAUUAUAAAGGAAAUAAACUAAUUGUUAACUUGCAUAGAUUACUUCUUAGUUUCCUAUGCUACCACCACUGCCAAGGGAGAAAAAAAUACAUCAUUUUGUAAUGUCUUUAGUAUUUCUUUAUAACUAGUGUUAAGGUUUUGUUAAUUUUAUUGUAUACAUUUGUAACAUUUAUUAGGAGCCUUUUAGGUUCCAAAACAAACAAAAGGCAUAAAAAAGUCUAGCUUAGAACCACUUUUCACUUGCUUUCAUUUUUAAUUUUAUUCACUUAACAGCUAACAUCUUUCUUGUUUCUUGUUUUUUCCAUUAUAUGGUUAUCGAUUCAACUCUUGCUAUAUUCCUUAAAUUUGUAUGUAUCAUCAGAAGAAAGAGAUGAACAAUUUAGUGUAGAUAUUUUAUUCUGGAGAAUAAUAUUCAAUUAAAUUAUUUCUACAGCAGGCCAGUAACAACUAGAUUAUUUGUCCUUUCUCAGUAUAAUUUUAAAGAGCAUUUUGUUUUAUUGUCACAAUUUGGUACCACUAGUCCCAGGUAACCAUUGGGCCAAAGGAUCAGUUGAGAAACAGUUAAGGAUGAAUUAGCAUAAGUUAUGGAACAGUGUUAGAAAACAACUCAAAAGUAUAUUCUUUAUUAAUGAGGUGGUCAUUAUUACAUUUGUGUCAAUGAAGGGCAGUGUAGUUAUUUUAAAAUGACUAAUAUUUUCUCCCCAAAUACAGAAUAAUUCAGAUGGGCAACCAAGUUUUCAAGAGACUGCUGUAGGUGAAGUCUGUCUAGCCAAGGCAGAACACUUACAGGAGUCCCUAACUGUGCCACCCUUGGAAUGGGUUAGUGUACAGGCUCAGAAUAUUGUGGAUUACAGUUUUUCAGAGAAAACUACCACAGAUGUAGACAAAAAUGAUCUCUGAAAGCAUUGCCAGCAGCCAGGUAUGUUCCUUAGAUUUCCACUUAGGUUUGGCAUUUUGGCAGAUAAGCUAAUCUUGUAUAAAGCAUCACAUUUUACUAUGCUUAGUGUUCCUGGGUUGUAUUUAUCUACAUUAUUAGAGGGAAUUUUUAUUUUAAAAAAAUUGUCAUUCAUGAGAAGAAUGGGAGUUCAUGCCACAUAGUAUUUUACCAAUUUAUAUAAAGUGGGAAAAGUCUUUAAUACUUCAUGAUCACUUGAAUUAAAGUUUUUGUAUCUCUGGAAAGUAGAAUAGUGCUUUCAUUUGAAUGAAAAGUGUUUAUAGAUUCAGAAAGAGAGAUGAUAUCUUUGUAUCUUGAUUUAUAUACAGACCAUUUCAGAGGAAGUUAAAUGUCUUACAAAUCCAAUACUUUCUAAUGCUCUAACAGUGUUGGCUAUUUAAAAGAACAUGUGGCAAGUUCUAUAUGAAUAUUCUUGGUCAUCUCGACUAAUUCUGAGGCAAUGAUGGACAGAGAUGCUACUUCUUAUUUAACUCUAGGCAUGUUGACUUUUCAAAGCGGUUUCCUUAUUUCUAAACAGAGAUGAUGAUCAAUGAGUUACUAAUUCUUUAGAGGAAAAAAUGCAUAAUUUGAGUGUGGAGUUGAUUUUAAUGACAGGGUAAUUCAAGUUGUUUGAUAAAUUUAUUACUAUAUUGUAAGAGAGAUCUUUGACCAUUUUUCUUCCUUUUUCUUGGACAUCACUUUCUUCCCUCCCCUUCUCUCUUUUAUGUUUUUAUCCUUGUUAAAUUUUAUGUUUACGUUACCAUCUUUCUUAUACUUUCCCCUGAUUUUUCUCUUUUAAUUCCUCUUUCAUUCUCUGCCUCUUCUCUUUCAGCUCUUUCUCUAAUUGUGCCUAUUCCUUGUUCAUAAGAAGUGGAGCUGUUAGUGGUAGAACCACUGCUCAUGGUUCUACCACUACAAAGUGGAAAGUAGAAAUACUUUGCACUUUGGCCACUGUUGCGUUUUUGCCAAGGUAAAGUUCCCCUGCCAUUUUGAAAUAGCUGAACAAGUUAAAGUAAUAUGUUCCAAAAACUGGAAGUGCCAUAAAAAACUAAAAAUAAAAAAAAAUUGUGACUAUAACUCCUACUGUCUUUAUGAAUACACGGGAUUCAGCAGCCAAGAUGCUCACAAAAUGGGAUUGCUAUAAAUAUGAUGGAUUCAGCACCUAAAUUUGGAAUAAUCAUGUCUUUUCUGUUAUGUGGGUAGAGAGAUUAUAUAUCUUUUCUCAAAGUAAAGUAUUUAAAACCUGUUUAAAUGAGGGUUUUGGCUGGCGUGGUGGCCCACACCUGUAAUCCCAGCACUUUGGGAAGCCAAGGUGGGAGUAUCACUUGAGGCCAGGAGUUUGAGACUAGCCUAGACAACAUAGCAAGAUCCUAUCUCUAGUUCAAAAAAAUAUUUUUAAUUAGGGUUUUGGUUUUUUAUGAUUUUGGGGGGUGGGGGAGAUAUUUGUUUUUUUGAGGCAGACGUUUAAACUUUUAGAUUUAUCCCAUCUUAAUAUUGAUUUAUAUUGACACUGCCUACUUACAAGAAUAAUUUGAGGCAGCAUAUUGCCCAUGUAUUUCAACUAUUUUCAUUUUUCUGUUGCAAAGCAGUCUUUGAUGGAAGACCCGGAAUCUUAUAGUUCUCAUAUCUGAGUCUUUCUGGAGUGUAUUUGGUGUCUGUGUGAUUGGUUCACCCAGAGGUCACCCAGAGGUCAAUUGAAACCUUCCUAAUUGUACUAUGGUAUUGAUUCUAUCCCCUCAAGUAUGAAAAAAUUAAAUUUUCAGACCAUUUUCAGUUGCUGCGAAUGUAGUUACACUAAGUUUUAUUUUAAACUAAAAUUCAAUAAACAGUGCAGCCAGGGAAGAUCUGCUAAACCAUGCCGUUAUUUGGAAAAUCAUUGCAAUAUAUUAACAACUGCUUCCUUCUAUGAUGUUUACUAGAUGGAGAAAAAUACUCCAUACCUAUAUUGCAAUUUUAUUUUUAUCUAGAAAAAGAAAAUAUUAGGCUUCAGACCCAACUGUGCAAAUUUCAUUUGCUUUCCAUCUCUUACUACUACCUCUGUGUCAUAAUUUAACACGUAACAUACAACUCCUGUCUCUUAAGGCAGCUACCAUAUGGUGUUUAUGUCAGACUGGAUAUAUUUAUCUAAUUUUGUGAAAUUAUUUUUUAGUUCCCAACACAAUUCUUGAAAGUAAUACCACUGUUGUUACUCUUUCUCCUUACAAUUUUUAUGUUGUUGAGAUGUAUCAGUUAUGUAUUAUAAUCAUGAAAUUGUAUUGGCCUCAAACCCAAAUUUUCUUUGUAGUCUAGGAUAGAUUUUUCAUGAAAGCUAUAUAGUUAUAACUGUGAUUGUACAGAUUGUUUAUUUGUUUUACAGCUAACAUUAAGCAUGAUUCCAGGUUUUUAAUUAUGUUCCAGCAACACUAGUGUUUCUUUAUAACUUAAAAUCAUAACCACUUUGAUAAUUUACCUUUGGAUCUGACCAGUGAUUCAUUUUUUUCUUGAAUAUACUUUGUGUUUGCUUUCUCAUCCCCGUUAAGUCUGAAACAUUAUUGACACCCCACAUCACUUACUCUGUUUAAAGACUUUACGAGUAGUGAGUCACAUGUUUAGGAUGAUCACUUUGGGAAAAAAAAAAUUAUAGAGUAAAGGGGAAAUGUUCUUGAGAGCUUUAUUAAAACCAUUAAUAUAUAAAAUGAAAAAAUAAUAAACAGAAGACACGAAGUGUCUCUCAAUAGUUUAGAAAGAAAGAUUUGGAACUUUAAGUAAAAAUGCUAGGUCAAGUAAAAAUCCUGAUGUAGAUUAGAUUAUCUUAAUCUUAUGAGCAUUUUUUUUUAAUUUGGUGAAGCUGUUUUGAAACUGCCUGUCCAUAUCAAUGCCAGACUAUCUCUCUACCUCUCAAAGAAAAUAAUUUGCAUUAAAAUUCCUUUUUUUGUUAUGUAAUGAAAGUAUAAAACAAGAAUUUGUACGUUACUCAGUGUGUACUGCAGUCAGAUAUAGUUAAAAUAAUUUUUCUGAUGCGUAAUUUUAACCACCAUUUCUGGAGUACCUAGUAUGUGCAGGCCAAGGCUUUGCCUAUAUUAUUCCCUUUAAUCCUCAAAGUAGCCUUGCAAAGAAGUUAUUUUCAUUUUACAGAAGAGUCAAGGAUUAGGGGGUUGAAGUGAGCUGCCUAGAGUCACAUACCUAAAGUCCAGGUGGAUCACUAUGUCUUGCUUUUUCAAAAGCAGUUCUUUCUACUACAGUACAAUAGUUUCAUGUUUUACAGUCCAUUAAAAUCCAAGACUUAUAAAAUAAACUAAAAAUACUCUUGAGGCAAUUACUAUUUCUAUGAUGGGCACUGGGACAAAUAUACUUGAACAUAACAAAGAACUAAAAAUACUGUGAAAAAAAGAUUUGUCUUAACGAUGACCUUGAAAGUUGCAUUGGGUUUUUAUUAUUGGUCCAGGUUUAAAACAUUUUAUCUAUUUAAAACAUAUGUUGUGUGUUUUAAGAAGUUAUGUUAUAAAUAACAGCAUUGUGGUUAAGAGCCCAGAGUCUGGGGCCAGGCUUCUUAGAUGCAAAUCCCAACUCUGUUAUUUUACUAAAUGUGUGACCUUGGGCAAGUUAAUUAACCUGUUUUGGUGUCCUCCUCUGUGAAAUGGAGUUAAUCGUGGUAUUUAACAGAAUUCAAAAUGUAGUGUGUUCUAAAGCGCUGUGCCUGGAGCAUCAUCACCACUAGGUGGUUAGGGAAGUAAAACACAUUUGGCACACAUCAUUCAAGAAUGGCCAGAAAAUCCAUGUCUUCCCACAAUAGGGACCAAUUUUUUGCCUUUCACCAGACAACCACUGAAUGUUAAGAAUCUACUGUGUGCUAAUAACUGUGUCCUUGCUGUAUGACAGAAGCUAUUUGGAGCGCUCUCAAGUGCUUAUUACAGCUAGUCAAGGAAACCGCAUAUAUAAAAUAAUACUGGAUACAAGACUAUACAAUUAAAUACUGGUGUAUCACUAA